GCAUUUGACCGCUCCUCCCUCCGCGUUGGAGGCGGAAUAGUGGGUUUUGCUGCAACCGGUUUAUUUUCCUUCUGUUUUCACCCAUUCUGGCACAAUCUGGCGCCAUCGUCCUUCUUGUGAGGCCAAGCCUGAAAAUGCGAAGCAGAGAGGCAGGACCAAAAUUGAGGCGAAUCCAGGAACCUGCCAAUGGGUCUCCGGGUGCGGUCUCUGAAACUGGAGGAUAUCGGGAGGAAAGGCUCUCCGAUGCGGAGAUAAUGGGGAAGCUCUUGGCAUGGUUGGCUGUAGGUAUGUGAUACCGGAGGAGCAGGAGUCAAAUAGGAUACGCCGACUUUUAAUUCAAGGAACCCUUUUCUGAAACACUUUGCCACAAUGAAGGAAAUAAGAUUACAGCCGAAGAUACAUAUUAAGGAUGAAGUUAAAGGAAGUAGAUCGUACAGCCAUGCAGGCAUGGAGCCCUGCCCAGAAUCACCCCAUUUACCUAGCAACAGGAACAUCUGCUCAGCAAUUGGAUGCAACAUUUAGUACGAAUGCUUCCCUUGAGAUAUUUGAAUUAGACCUCUCUGAUCCAUCCUUGGAUAUGAAAUCUUGUGCCACAUUCUCCUCUUCUCACAGGUACCACAAGUUGAUUUGGGGGCCUUAUAAAAUGGAUUCCAAAGGAGAUGUCUCUGGAGUUCUGAUUGCAGGUGGUGAAAAUGGAAAUAUUAUUCUCUAUGAUCCUUCUAAAAUUAUAGCUGGAGACAAGGAAGUUGUGAUUGCCCAGAAUGACAAGCAUACUGGCCCAGUGAGAGCCUUGGAUGUGAACAUUUUCCAGACUAAUCUGGUAGCUUCUGGUGCUAAUGAAUCUGAAAUCUACAUAUGGGAUCUAAAUAAUUUUGCAACCCCAAUGACACCAGGAGCCAAAACACAGCCGCCAGAAGAUAUCAGCUGCAUUGCAUGGAACAGACAAGUUCAGCAUAUUUUAGCAUCAGCCAGUCCCAGUGGCCGGGCCACUGUAUGGGAUCUUAGAAAAAAUGAGCCAAUCAUCAAAGUCAGUGACCAUAGUAACAGAAUGCAUUGUUCUGGGUUGGCAUGGCAUCCUGAUGUUGCUACUCAGAUGGUCCUUGCCUCCGAGGAUGACCGGUUACCAGUGAUCCAGAUGUGGGAUCUUCGAUUUGCUUCCUCUCCACUUCGUGUCCUGGAAAACCAUGCCAGGGGGAUUUUGGCAAUUGCUUGGAGCAUGGCAGAUCCUGAAUUGUUACUGAGCUGUGGAAAAGAUGCUAAGAUUCUCUGCUCCAAUCCAAACACAGGAGAGGUGUUAUAUGAACUUCCCACCAACACACAGUGGUGCUUCGAUAUUCAGUGGUGUCCCCGAAAUCCUGCUGUCUUAUCAGCUGCUUCGUUUGAUGGGCGUAUCAGUGUUUAUUCUAUCAUGGGAGGUAGCACAGAUGGUUUAAGACAGAAACAAGUUGACAAGCUUUCAUCAUCUUUUGGGAAUCUUGAUCCCUUUGGCACAGGACAGCCCCUUCCUCCGUUACAAAUUCCACAGCAGACUGCUCAGCAUAGUAUAGUGCUGCCUCUGAAGAAGCCGCCCAAGUGGAUUCGAAGGCCUGUUGGUGCUUCUUUUUCAUUUGGAGGCAAACUGGUUACGUUUGAGAAUGUCAGAAUGCCUUCUCAUCAGGGAGCUGAGCAGCAGCAGCAGCAGCACCAUGUGUUCAUUAGUCAGGUUGUAACAGAAAAGGAGUUCCUCAGCCGAUCAGACCAACUUCAGCAGGCUGUGCAGUCACAAGGAUUUAUCAAUUAUUGCCAAAAAAAAAUUGAUGCUUCUCAGACUGAAUUUGAGAAAAAUGUGUGGUCCUUUUUGAAGGUAAACUUUGAGGAUGAUUCUCGUGGAAAAUACCUUGAACUUCUAGGAUACAGAAAAGAAGAUCUAGGAAAGAAGAUUGCUUUGGCCUUGAACAAAGUGGAUGGAGCCAAUGUGGCUCUUAAAGACUCUGACCAAGUAGCACAGAGUGAUGGGGAGGAGAGCCCUGCUGCUGAAGAGCAGCUCUUGGGAGAGCACAUUAAAGAGGAAAAAGAAGAAUCUGAAUUUCUACCCUCAUCUGGAGGAACAUUUAAUAUCUCUGUCAGUGGGGACAUUGAUGGUUUAAUUACUCAGGCUUUGCUGACGGGCAAUUUUGAGAGUGCUGUUGACCUUUGUUUACAUGAUAACCGCAUGGCCGAUGCCAUUAUAUUGGCCAUAGCAGGUGGACAAGAACUCUUGGCUCGAACCCAGAAAAAAUACUUCGCAAAAUCCCAAAGCAAAAUUACCAGGCUCAUCACUGCAGUGGUGAUGAAGAACUGGAAAGAGAUUGUUGAGUCUUGUGAUCUUAAAAAUUGGAGAGAGGCUUUAGCUGCAGUAUUGACUUAUGCAAAGCCGGAUGAAUUUUCAGCCCUUUGUGAUCUUUUGGGAACCAGGCUUGAAAAUGAAGGAGAUAGCCUCCUGCAGACUCAAGCAUGUCUCUGCUAUAUUUGUGCAGGGAAUGUAGAGAAAUUAGUUGCAUGUUGGACUAAAGCUCAAGAUGGAAGCCACCCUUUGUCACUUCAGGAUCUGAUUGAGAAAGUUGUCAUCCUGCGAAAAGCUGUGCAACUCACUCAAGCCAUGGACACUAGUACUGUAGGAGUUCUCUUGGCUGCGAAGAUGAGUCAGUAUGCCAAUUUGUUGGCAGCUCAGGGCAGUAUUGCUGCAGCCUUGGCUUUUCUUCCUGACAACACCAACCAGCCAAAUAUCAUGCAGCUUCGUGACAGACUUUGUAGAGCACAAGGAGAGCCUGUAGCAGGACAUGAAUCACCUAAAAUUCCGUACGAGAAACAGCAGCUCCCCAAGGGCAGGCCUGGACCAGUUGCUGGCCACCACCAGAUGCCAAGAGUUCAAACUCAACAAUAUUAUCCCCAUGGAGAAAAUCCUCCACCUCCGGGUUUCAUAAUGCAUGGAAAUGUUAAUCCAAAUGCUGCUGGUCAGCUUCCCACAUCUCCAGGUCAUAUGCACACCCAGGUACCACCUUAUCCACAGCCACAGCCUUAUCAACCAGCCCAGCCGUAUCCCUUCGGAACAGGGGGGUCAGCAAUGUAUCGACCUCAGCAGCCUGUUGCUCCUCCUACUUCAAACGCUUACCCUAACACCCCUUACAUAUCUUCUGCUUCUUCCUAUACUGGGCAGUCUCAGCUGUACGCAGCACAGCACCAGGCCUCUUCACCUACCUCCAGCCCUGCUACUUCUUUCCCUCCUCCCCCUUCCUCUGGAGCAUCCUUCCAGCAUGGCGGACCAGGAGCUCCACCAUCAUCUUCAGCUUAUGCACUGCCUCCUGGAACAACAGGUACACUGCCUGCUGCCAGUGAGCUGCCUGCGUCCCAAAGAACAGGUCCUCAGAAUGGUUGGAAUGACCCUCCAGCUUUGAACAGAGUACCCAAAAAGAAGAAGAUGCCUGAAAACUUCAUGCCUCCUGUUCCCAUCACAUCACCAAUCAUGAACCCGUUGGGUGACCCCCAGUCACAAAUGCUGCAGCAACAGCCUUCAGCUCCAGUACCACUGUCAAGCCAGUCUUCAUUCCCACAGCCACAUCUUCCAGGUGGCCAGCCCUUCCAUGGCGUACAGCAACCUCUUGGUCAAACAGGCAUGCCACCAUCUUUUUCAAAGCCCAAUAUUGAAGGUGCCCCAGGGGCUCCUAUUGGAAAUACCUUCCAGCAUGUGCAGUCUUUGCCAACAAAAAAAAUUACCAAGAAACCUAUUCCAGAUGAGCACCUCAUUCUAAAGACCACAUUUGAGGAUCUUAUUCAGCGCUGCCUUUCUUCAGCAACAGACCCUCAAACCAAGAGGAAGCUAGAUGAUGCCAGCAAACGUUUGGAGUUUCUGUAUGAUAAACUUAGGGAACAGACACUUUCACCAACAAUCACCAGUGGUUUACACAACAUUGCAAGGAGCAUUGAAACUCGAAACUACUCAGAAGGAUUGACCAUGCAUACCCACAUAGUUAGCACCAGCAACUUCAGUGAGACCUCUGCUUUCAUGCCAGUUCUCAAAGUUGUUCUCACCCAGGCCAAUAAGCUGGGUGUCUAAAAGGACAGCUUCUCUUCCACUCAAUAUUGCCAUUUUUCCAAAGAAACAUGUUAAAAAAAAAAAUUAUAAGACAUGGACUAGUCCUCAUUAGCAUGUUUGCAUAGCAACCAGUCAAGAGCAUUUACACUAUUUCUGCUGAUAUACUCACCUUAGAACUGCUCAGAACCCUGGUGCUUUAUUUUUGUUUUAAUCUUUUGUUGCCAGUGAUGAUUUUCCUAUUCUGCAAAUAGUGUAUUUCCUGGAUUACACAUAGUAUGGUUUCCUGAAGUAUUCUGAUAAAUGUGUUUUUUAAAACCUCAAUAUACUUUUUAGAAAAGGAGCAUCUGGUUAUGCAUAAAGCAGAGCUAAAACUAAAUUUCUUUCAUGUCCUCCCUACUUCCUCAGUGUCAAUCAGAUUAAAGUGUGUAAUCCUAUUUUAUGUGUGUAUAGUCUUUUUUGAAACAGCUGCUUAAAAUUUAGUUUAUUUUUUGUGUCUUAGGAUUCCUGAGUAAAUAACUACAUCUACAAACUGCUACAUGGGUUUUAGCAGAUAUUAAUAAAAAUGGGAUCACUGGCUUUAACUAUA